GCAGAUUACGGUUGCACCGUAAAAGGAGAGGUUCUGUUCCGUCGCGGGAUUUCGCCAUGGCCCGGGGCCCCAAGAAGCACUUGAAGCGUGUUGCAGCGCCGAAGCAUUGGAUGCUGGAUAAACUAACUGGUGUAUUUGCACCUCGUCCAUCGACAGGUCCUCACAAGCUGAGGGAAUGUCUUCCCCUGAUAGUCUUCCUCAGGAAUAGACUCAAGUAUGCAUUGACUGGAGAUGAGGUAAAGAAGAUAUGUAUGCAACACUUCCUCAAAAUUGAUGGCAAGGUUCGAGUGGACAUCACAUACCCUGCUGGAUUCAUAGAUGUCAUCAGCAUUGAGAAAACAGGUGAGCAUUUCCGCCUGGUCUAUAAUACCAAGGGCUGUUUUGCUGUUCAUCGUAUCACAGUGGAAGAGGCAAAGUACAAGUUGUGCAAAGUGAGGAAGAUUACUGUGGGGACAAAGGGAAUUCCACACCUGGUGACUCAUGAUGCUCGAACCAUUCGCUACCCAGAUCCUCUCAUCAAGGUGAACGAUACUGUGCAGAUUGAUUUAGGGACUGGGAAGAUAACCAGCUUUAUCAAAUUUGACACAGGCAAUGUAUGUAUGGUGAUUGCUGGAGCUAACCUCGGUCGUGUUGGUGUGAUCACAAACAGGGAAAGACAUCCUGGUUCUUGCGAUGUGGUACAUGUGAAGGAUGCCAACGGCAACAGCUUUGCCACAAGGAUUUCCAACAUUUUUGUCAUUGGCAAUGGUAAUAAACCUUGGAUUUCCCUGCCCAGGGGAAAGGGCAUCCGACUUACUAUUGCUGAAGAGAGAGACAAGAGGCUGGCUGCCAAACAGAGCAGUGGCUAA